GUCAUUUUUGUCACUGACAUAGACUAGAUUUAUGCAAGUUUUUCUCUGUGAGGUCUUCAGCAGCUUCUGGAGGAAAGUAUUGGUCUGAACACAUGGGCAUUGCUUUUGGGACUUUGGGUUAACUUCCACCAUGGAUUUCUUUUCUUUGUUUUUGUUUUUUUGUUUUGUUUUGUUUUUGAUAUGGAGUUUCACUCUGUCGCCCAGGCUGUAAUGCAGUGGCGCGAUCUUGGCUCACUGCAACCUCCACCUCCUGGGUUCAAGCGAUUCUCGUGUCUCGGCCUCCUGAGUAGCUGGGAUUACAGGUGCCCACCACCAUGCCUGGCUAAUUUUUGUGUUUUUAGUAGAGAGUUUCACCAUGUUGGCCAGGCUGGUCUCAAACCCCUGACCUCAGGUGAUCCACCCCCCGCCUCGGCCUCCCAAAGUGCUGGGAUUACAGUCGUGAGCCACCGCACCCAGCCUGUUUUUUUUUUUUUUUUCCAGUGCAUGGUUAUAUGUAUCUUCACUUACCUCUUGAAUUUUACUCUAAGUCAGUGAGAUAAAACGCAACACUGUGUAUAUUUCUCCCUCUCCUUGCUGAUUCUGUUCACUAGGUCUUGCAUUCAUUCAUUCAUUUAUUCAUUGGUCCAUUCAUUGAUCCAAAACCACUUAUUAAGAACCUACUAUUGCUAGGCACUGUGCCAAGCUUUCAGGAAGCAGUGAAGCUUGCGGGACUUUUCUCUUCCUUACCGGAACUCAAGAGUUUGAAGGUAGCCUAAAUGUUCAUGCCGCGUGGUGGGUGCUGUGGUAGGGAGAGGGCAGGGGGCCUUGGGCACUCACAGCAACAGAUCCCAUCUUGUGACCUCUGCUUUCUUCUCAGCCGCUGAGCCCACACAUCCUCCCCUAUCAUCUUUUUGAUCUUUGCCUUUGUGCUCUGGGGAUUCACAAUCUGUUGUGGAUGUACGUUCCUUUUUGAUCCCACUUCCUCCUUACCCAGGGAACCUGAAACAUCCUUGCUCCUCUUACGAAAUACCAGAUUAAGAUGAAAACUGGUAUUGGCUUUUGAAGAAUUGUCCAGAAAAUUAUUGGGCUGAUGACUGGGGUGGGUAGAAGAUGGGGGCUGGUAAUUUUUGAAGAUGAAAUAGGUGAUGUUUAUGGUCCUUCCUUAAGUUAUACCUGCUGAAAAGCUGAAGUAGACACUGUCGUUGAGUAAAGGUCUGGGCCGCCACUCGGAGAGAGGGUGCAUUGCUAUACUGGGAAAGCGUCUUCCCUUUUCUGAGCCCUACUCAGUCCAACAAAGCAGUUCAUCUGUUUAUAGAAAGUGAGUGUGUUGAAAUCAUCAUAGUGAAGUGAACUCAGUGAGCAGAAGUCUGAGCUUUCAGAUUCCCUCAAAGGAAAUAACAUGGUGACAGAUCCAAAAAUCCUAAUUUAAAACUUAUCAGCCCUGAGAACUAAGCUUAAGGCCAGCUUCAUAUUUUCUCAUUUUUAAAAAAUUAAAAAUUUUUUUCUCAACAGAUUAAGUUGUUAAGUAGCAUAAAGUGUUAUCUGGGUUAUGUUUGAAGCAUGUUCUUGCUAGUUUUGCCAGGCUGAUAUUUGCAGGAGGGUGUUUUAGGGCUCCAGGUGGCUUUAUCCAGUCAGGAUCUAGCCUGUCUGAUUUAAGUCCUCUGUUGGCAACAUUGGAAAUGGACUCUGAACAACCACGCAAAGAAACUUAUGACUGGCUCAUCGUUCAGAGAGAUGCCAAGAGGGCAAGAGCCAGGGCCACCUGGGGUGUCAGUGUUCCAAGCUGGUGGGCCUUCUGCAUCCCAUCUCAGGUAGCCCAGCCCUCCCAGUCUUGGGUGGCCUUGGCUCUCCAUAUACGUUUCAUGAAUAUCUGUUUGGGCCAGAUGUUUCCCACCCCUGUCAGCCAGCAGAUACCAAGACCUGGGUCCCGUAUUAUAGACAUGGCUACUGGGGGCCCACCCUUGUGUUUCGGUGCCUCUCUGAGCACUGAAAUCAUUGAAAUCCAGGGAGCCCUGUUUUUACCUUCAGAUCUAGCCAUUGCAUUAUGUGUCUGUUUAAAUUCCCAAACAGAAAUAUUGAAUCAGAAAAUCCCCUCUUCUUACGUAUCCCAAAGGUUGAUAUUGAGUAAUAUUUGGUUGUAAUUGUGGAAGGGGUCCUUAGGCAAGCAGUCUUCCCAGGCCAGAAUUUCUGAGUUUUUUCACAGAAGCACUGCCAGUUCUAGAAUUUAAGUAUCAUAAAACAGUCAGGUCAGCUGUCAUUAAAAUGUCUAAAAUUCUAUUACUAUCUAUUGCUUCCACUUCUGAUCCACACUUAUCAGACCUUGACAUCUUUAUACGACAGGAUGUGAACUUGAGCCCAUAACAACUUAGUCUUCAUAACAAACUUAAUCAGGCUUAAGAGGAGAAAGUUCUUGCAACAGAGCCUAGAGUUAGUUCCCAAACUUGGGUGUCUGUCAGAAUCGUGGGUAACAGAUUUUUAAGACCUCAUUUCCAGCUUUUUAUGUAGUAGGUCUGGGUUGGGGUUCAUGAGCGUGUAUUUGUUUUUAUCCCCCUUUCCCGUAUUUUUCAUGAAUGAACCUACAUUCUUAAGCACCAAAACUUGCUUCUAUUGCAGGCAGUCCAAGGACCACUCUUUGAGAAAUACUGACCUAGAGUGUGCUCCUUGCCAGUUUUCCUCAUUUAGUGGGGAAAAAGAAGUUAGAUAUAAAAACCUCCCUGACUGCGACUUCAAACAGUGGAGGUGAUGGGGUUGCUCUGAUUUAGAAAGACAGAGUUUGUGAUCUACGGGGAAUUGACUAGAACCUCAGAUCCUCCAAAGCACACCUCAUCCUGGCUAAAUCUCAUUCUCUCAGGAGGGAGUCCUCUGAGGCCCAACACCAGCUCAGAACGAUUCAAAAACUCCCCUGUACUUUUUCUCUGUAAAAGACAAAGGACAGGACAAUUCCCAAGGCUCAGAGCCUUUGUGUAGUCAGUUUUCUGUUGAACUGAUUUUGGAAGUAGCACAAAGUAGCAAGAGCUCUUACUUUUACAUGGAACUAUGCUUCCCUAACCUGGCUCAUCUUCAUAAUUAGUUCUUAAGCUUUAAAACAGUCAGAAAUUUGCAUUUUUUAAAACCACCCAGAAUGAUUUUCAUGUACACAAACUUUUGAAGCAGUGUGGUAGUAAGUAGUGUUCUUUAAGUUCAACCUUGAUAGGAAGUUCCCCACCAGGUCUACUCUUUUUAUUUCCAUAUCUCUAAGUUGGUUCAUGCAACAGUCAUCAAGACUAACUGAUUCUCAGCUCCCUGUGUGUGUCUCUUCUACCAUAGAGCUGUGCAGUCUCUUGCCUGAAUUUGUUGUGGUGACUUCUGGAGUAGUCUCUCUGCCUUUAGCUACCUCUUCUCUAGUUCAUCCUCCCCCUGUGACCUAAUCCUGUCGCUUCCCUGAACAGAAGAAGCACUGAUUGCACCCAUUGCCCACAUGAUAAACUUGCACAGGGUCAAAGGCCUUGUGGCAUCUCACUCUUGUCCCUCAAACUUAGCACACUUUCCCAUAAGCUGUUCUCUCUGCCUGGGACUGCCCACUGGGAACCUUCCUUCCUUAAUCUGUUCAGCCCUUUACACAUACUUGCACUUCUAGAACAAAUAUUUUCUGCUGCUUGAAGCCUUACCUAACUCUCCCAAGUAGAUUUUUUCUCUUUUUGUUCUCUAGUCUUCCUAACAGUCUCCCAAAUAGCAUUAUCAUAAGGGAUUAUAUAAGACAGUAUUUGUUAUAUCUCUUUCAAGAACCAAGGUCCUCUGAGAGAGGAUGAGGGCAGAAUUUUGUUUAUCUUCAUAAGGACUUACUGUAGUGACUGGCAUGAAAUAGGUGCUUAAUUUUGACUGUGUGAAAACUGAACUGUACCAGAAACAGGCCAGUAUAAUGGGCAUCUUUUUUUGUGAUUGUUUCUGAGUUAAACCUGUAGGAGGAUUACAUCGAGAGGCCUUUCCCGGUCUCAAACCAUGAAUUAUGUGGGACAGCUGGCUGGGCAGGUGAUUGUCACUGUGAAGGAACUCUACAAGGGCAUUAACCAGGCCACCCUCUCUGGGUGCAUUGAUGUCAUCGUGGUACAGCAGCAGGAUGGCAGCUAUCAGUGUUCACCUUUUCACGUUCGGUUUGGAAAGCUGGGAGUCCUGAGAUCCAAAGAGAAAGUGAUUGAUAUAGAAAUCAACGGCAGUGCAGUGGAUCUUCACAUGAAGUUGGGUGAUAACGGAGAAGCUUUCUUUGUUGAGGAGACUGAAGAAGAAUAUGAAAAGCUUCCUGCUUACCUUGCCACCUCACCAAUUCCUACUGAAGAUCAGUUCUUUAAAGAUAUUGACACCCCUUUGGUGAAAUCGGGUGGAGAUGAAACACCAUCUCAGAGUUCAGACAUCUCACACGUCUUGGAAACAGAGACAAUUUUUACUCCAAGUUCUGUGAAAAAGAAAAAACGAAGGAGAAAGAAAUACAAACAGGACAGUAAGAAGGAAGAGCAGGCCGCAUCUGCUGCUGCAGAAGACACAUGUGAUGUAGGCGUGAGCUCCGAUGAUGACAAGGGGGCCCAGGCAGCACGAGGAUCUUCAAAUGCUUCCUUGAAAGAAGAAGAAUGUAAAGAGCCUUUGCUCUUCCAUUCUGGGGAUCAUUACCCCUUAUCUGAUGGAGAUUGGUCCCCUUUAGAGACCACCUAUCCCCAGACAGCGUGUCCUAAGAGUGAUUCAGAGCUGGAGGUGAAACCUGCGGAGAGCCUGCUCAGAUCAGAGUCUCACAUGGAGUGGACGUGGGGCGGAUUCCCAGAGUCCACCAAGGUCAGCAAAAGAGAACGAUCUGACCAUCAUCCUAGGACAGCUACAAUUACACCAUCAGAAAAUACUCAUUUUCGGGUAAUUCCCAGUGAGGACAACCUCAUCAGUGAAGUUGAGAAGGAUGCUUCCAUGGAAGACACUGUCUGUACCAUAGUGAAGCCCAAACCCAGAGCCCUGGGUACACAGAUGAGCGACCCAACAUCUGUGGCAGAGCUUCUCGAACCUCCUCUUGAGAGUACUCAGAUUUCAUCUAUGUUAGAUGCUGACCACCUUCCCAACGCAGCCUUAGCGGAGGCGCCCUCAGAAUCCAAACCGGCAGCUAAAGUAGACUCGCCGUCAAAGAAGAAAGGUGUUCACAAAAGAAGCCAACACCAGGGACCUGAUGAUAUUUACCUUGAUGACUUAAAGGGUCUAGAACCUGAAGUUGCAGCUCUUUAUUUCCCUAAAAGUGAAUCGGAGCCCGGUUCCAGGCAGUGGCCCGAGUCUGACACACUCUCUGGCUCCCAGUCCCCACAGUCCGUGGGAAGCGCAGCUGCAGAUAGCGGCACCGAGUGCCUCUCAGAUUCUGCCAUGGACUUGCCUGACGUUACCCUCUCCCUUUGCGGGGGCCUCAGUGAAAAUGGAGAAAUUUCAAAAGAAAAAUUCAUGGAGCAUAUCAUUACUUAUCACGAAUUUGCAGAAAACCCUGGACUUAUAGACAAUCCUAACCUUGUAAUAAGGAUAUAUAAUCGUUACUAUAACUGGGCUUUGGCAGCUCCCAUGAUCCUUAGCUUGCAAGUAUUCCAGAAGAGCUUGCCUAAGGCCACAGUUGAGUCCUGGGUGAAAGACAAGAUGCCAAAGAAAUCUGGUCGCUGGUGGUUUUGGCGAAAGAGAGAAAGCAUGACCAAACAGCUGCCAGAAUCCAAGGAGGGAAAAUCUGAGGCACCGCCAGCCAGUGACCUGCCAUCCAGCUCCAAGGAGCCGGCCGGUGCCAGGCCGGCCGAGAAUGACUCCUCGAGUGACGAGGGAUCACAGGAGCUCGAAGAAUCCAUCACAGUGGACCCCAUCCCCACAGAGCCCCUGAGCCACGGCAGCACAACUUCAUAUAAGAAGUCUCUCCGCCUCUCCUCAGACCAGAUCGCAAAACUGAAGCUCCACGAUGGCCCAAAUGAUGUUGUGUUUAGUAUUACAACCCAGUAUCAAGGCACCUGUCGCUGUGCAGGGACCAUUUACCUGUGGAACUGGAAUGACAAGAUCAUCAUUUCUGAUAUUGAUGGGACAAUAACCAAGUCGGAUGCUUUGGGACAGAUUCUCCCACAGCUGGGCAAAGACUGGACCCACCAGGGUAUAGCAAAGCUCUACCAUUCCAUCAAUGAGAAUGGCUACAAGUUUCUGUACUGCUCGGCUCGUGCCAUCGGCAUGGCCGACAUGACCCGUGGCUACCUGCACUGGGUCAAUGACAAGGGCACAAUCUUGCCCCGGGGCCCCCUGAUGCUGUCCCCCAGCAGCUUGUUCUCCGCCUUCCACAGAGAAGUGAUAGAAAAGAAACCAGAGAAGUUCAAAAUUGAGUGUCUAAAUGAUAUCAAGAAUCUGUUUGCCCCGUCUAAGCAGCCCUUCUAUGCUGCCUUUGGAAACCGUCCAAAUGAUGUCUAUGCCUACACACAAGUUGGAGUUCCAGACUGUAGAAUAUUCACCGUGAACCCCAAGGGUGAAUUAAUACAAGAAAGAACCAAAGGAAACAAGUCAUCGUAUCACAGGCUGAGUGAGCUCGUGGAGCAUGUGUUCCCCCUUCUCAGUAAGGAGCAGAAUUCCGCUUUUCCCUGCCCGGAGUUCAGCUCCUUCUGCUACUGGCGAGACCCGAUCCCUGAAGUGGACCUGGAUGACCUGUCUUGAGGCGGCACCUCAGUGGGUGGGCAGGGCUUGGUCCCCCUCCCCACAGCAAGGGAAGGCAGCUGGCUCUUCUGCUGACCUCAGAUACCAGCCUUCCCCAGCGGGGACGGGUGCUUCUGGAGCUGGUCCCGCCAUCCUCCUUUGCCUUCCCAGGCCAGCUGCUCAGGCUCGGCAGGUCUGCAGCUCAGCUCCUGGAAGGAGAAGGGAGGAACUGGGCCUGGGGCUGGAGGCCUGGGAUCCCUCCUUUGUGGGUCGCACACAUGUUUCCUGCUGUGAGCUGGGGCCUCCUUCCAUUGCAUCAUUUUAAAGGAAGAAAAAAGCAGCUAAAAAAGAGUGGACCAAAACACUGCACACAGUGAAGUGUUCCAGUUUCCACUGGGCAGUUGAGGUGGCUUCUGUAACCAGGGCUGUCUUCAGAUGUCAGGGUCCCUGAACUGCUGCGGGCCCAGUCAGUGAUGCUGGCUGAAGCUGCCUGUGCACGUUUCUUCUCUGGUCGCCUCAUUUCCUGCUACACUGAAGGGGUCAGCUGCUCCAGUGGGCCAAGUUGGGCAGGACCCCCGCCCCUGCAGGGCCCAUGCACCAGAGCCACUGAGCCCAGUCCCAUAAACCUGGCCCUCUUUGGGGAAAGAUCCCCACAGAGCAUCCUCCUCUCAUCUGUGACAACUCCACGAGCCCUUAAUUUCUUAGUCCUCACCAGAAGAACAGGUCUCACAAGUAUAUAUUUGAUGUCUGUAAUAAAAGUGGGAAGGUGGGUCUUAAAACAGACCAAACCCCGCCCCGCCCCCAACAACUCUGCUUUUAGGGAGGCCUCCGAAAUGCAGAUAGGCGGUUGAGUGGGGUCCUGGGAAGAGCGCUGAAUCCCUCUGCUUGCUGCCUGGUGUGGGCCUUUGGAAAGCAUCUUGCCUUGGGACAGGAUUUCUAAAAUUCUGUGAUUCAGAUUUGUCAGGGAAGCACAGUGAAGCUUGCUUAAAGGCACUGGCCAGCAGUGUGUGACUUUGGCUUUUGGGAUCACACCCUGUAAUCGGGCCCGUGGAAGCAGCGUCAAAGAGGGGUCUUGGAGCUCCUAUGGAGCAGACUGCCCCCCGAGCAGUGUCCCCAGCCUAGCCCUGUGAGACCCCAUGGGGACACGGGUGCCUAUGUAUUUUCACUAAAAUAUACAUGGUAGCUCCAUUUACUGAUGCGGUUGUAAUGAGCUCACAUCGUGUCUGAAGAGAUGGCACCAGGGAAAGGUGUGCCAUAAGCUGCUCCAGAGCUUUUGGUAUGCUGAGUGUUGACAGAGCUGCACUCUUAACAUCAAGAGAACUGUCAGGAGCCCAGAACCAACCCCAGGUCUUGGUCUCCAUUGGCGAGAACACAGGACGUGGUGGUUCCUGAGCAGAGAGGGAUCUGCAGAUACAGGCUUGGCGCUCGGGGUGGUCUCGUGGCCAACUCUUCAUGCCCCUGCCGUUGUAGUGGAACCUCUACAUGUUUUAGUUUGCUUCACCUAAAAUAAUGCUGAUCUAGAGAUAGAGAAAUAGGGGUGGUUAUUUUUCCAGAUUGGAGAGUUGAAAGUCCCUGACUGAUUUCAGCCAUUUUCCUAGUGCUUGUCGGAUGCAGAGACAAUGUUGAAAUCCCCUAAACACAGUUCUCAGUGGCAAAACCUAGGAAGGCUCAUGUUCCCAGAGAAGGGACCACAUGAGCCUUCUCCCAUGCAAAGCUUCCCCCAGCUUAAAUAGUUGAUAAGGACUAAUUGUUUAAUGAGUUUAUUUAUCUACAGUAGGUUAGGGAUCCUGGGUUCUGUUUAUAUGAAGUUCUUCCCAGUUUGUGAAUUCUAGUACAGCAGCCAUGCAGCCACCUUAUUUCAUAGAUGCCAUCUGUGUGUCCUCUUGACUACCUUCUAUUUAGAGGAAGAAUGAGAGCUUUGUGUGUUUAACUGAGCUUAUAGUAGGACUUCUUUGCAUAUGUAUGGUACUGAAAAAUCUUAAUAUACAUCUUUAAUCCUUUUUAGGUUGUCCUUUAAAGAGUUUUUGACUAGUUUCUUUUUCUUGACAGCUCUUCUCUUUGGACACAUGGGCCUUCUUAGAGGGUUCAGUCUAGGACCCGGCUCUCCUGGCCCUGUGUUGAGGGUAGCUGGUCCCUCUGUCCCUGUGUCUGCUAGCACUAGACUUUGUUGCUGCAGAUUGAUCCAGUGGGUACAUAGGCUAAUUAAUGUGAGUCUUUUUCCUUGUUUAAAGGAGUCCCUCUUGCUGAAAGUAGAUGAUUACUAUUGCUGUAGUGUUAGGAAAGUAUUAAGUUUGUGCUGAAAAUCCAUUGCCAUUUGGUACAAAUGACAUUUGUUCUUUCUGUGAAAGAGAUGCCCUCGAGUGUGUUUGUACACAAACCCUUAGGAUGGUGAGUUGAAGCAUCACCCUCGCGCUAUCUUCAGUGACGGGUGACGGCUCAGGGAGAUGGCAGGCAGAUUGGGCUCUAAGUCAUUAUUCUCUCAGUUACUCCAUUGGUGAAAUGGCCCUUUCCCUCUUUGCAGUUCAGUCUAAGUCUCGUAUUUGCUUUGCUGUCUGUGUGCUGAAGCUCGUCCCGUGUGAGUUGCUGUCUGCCCCUUGUCAGGCUGUGAGGUGCUCGUGUAGACCUGGAGCAUGCAGGCUGCCUCCGUUUUUGGGUACUGUGUUGUGUUUUGCUCUGUCUAAAAACAUCUGCAUAGUUUUCAACUGGAAAAAGAAAAAACUUAAAAAUGGGAUGUCCUAAAAUGAAAGCUGCUCAAAGUCACAGAACAACCGAGGGACAAAGGAGAUUGGAUGACUGGGAAGCGCUGGCCCGGAACAGCCCCUGCAACUGUGGGGCCUGCACACAGCCCUUCCACAGUUGGCACUGCAGGUGCAGGCCAACCCUUUAAAGAAUAAACAAGGAAGUCAGCUCUUUCACUUUUUACAAGUUGGCAAAAACAGACUUCCGGGGAAUUUCGAUGUUUUCCCGUGUUGUAGAGCUUCCAGGGUUUAAUAAAACUGGUUAAAAAUUGAGUCUUUCCCUGAAGUAAGUGCUCUUUCCAGAUGAAAACUACUCUUUUGGUUUUGUUUGAAAGUAAGAAAGGGAGGGGAAACUUUGCUCUUUUAAUAAUUAUGUUCAGCCUAUGAUGAAGUAUUUGAUUAUUAGACAGCAAUGUCACUAAUAAGUUUUAAGUUGUCCAAAGUUAAUUGUAAACAUCAUCAGUACAGUACUCUUAGUUACAGUAAAGCAAUUGUUGCAAGAUGAAUGGCUAAUAUUUUGGUGCAGUGUUUGAUGUUCAAAACAAAAUGUUACAACAAUAAACGAACAUAACAUAAACUGAA